GUCUCUGGGCGCGGCCAUGUUGGAGGCUCCGGGCCCGAGUGAUGGCUGCGAGCUCAGCAACCCCAGCGCCAGCAGAGUCAGCUGUGCCGGGCAGAUGCUGGAAGUGCAGCCAGGAUUGUAUUUCGGUGGGGCCGCGGCCGUCGCGGAGCCAGAUCACCUGAGGGAAGCGGGCAUCACGGCCGUGCUAACAGUGGACUCGGAGGAGCCCAGCUUCAAGGCGGGGCCUGGGGUCGAGGAUCUAUGGCGCCUCUUCGUGCCAGCGCUGGACAAACCCGAGACGGACCUACUCAGCCAUCUGGACCGGUGCGUGGCCUUCAUCGGUCAGGCCCGCGCUGAGGGCCGUGCGGUGUUGGUGCACUGGUCUCUUUUUCAGUCAUGCAGGAGUCAGUCGAAGUGUGGCCAUAAUAACUGCUUUUCUCAUGAAGACUGACCAACUUCCCUUUGAAAAAGCCUAUGAAAAGCUCCAGAUUCUCAAACCAGAGGCUAAGAUGAAUGAGGGGUUUGAGUGGCAACUGAAAUUAUACCAGGCAAUGGGAUACGAAGUGGAUACCUCUAGUGCAAUUUAUAAGCAAUAUCGUUUACAAAAGGUUACAGAGAAGUAUCCAGAAUUGCAGAAUUUACCUCAAGAACUCUUUGCUGUUGACCCAACUACCGUUUCACAAGGAUUGAAAGAUGAGGUUCUCUACAAGUGUAGAAAGUGCAGGCGAUCAUUAUUUCGAAGUUCUAGUAUUCUGGAUCACCGUGAAGGAAGUGGACCUAUAGCCUUUGCCCACAAGAGAAUGACACCAUCUUCCAUGCUUACCACAGGGAGGCAAGCUCAAUGUACAUCUUAUUUCAUUGAACCUGUACAGUGGAUGGAAUCUGCUUUGUUGGGAGUGAUGGAUGGACAGCUUCUUUGCCCAAAAUGCAGUGCCAAGUUGGGUUCCUUCAACUGGUAUGGUGAACAGUGCUCUUGUGGUAGGUGGAUAACACCUGCUUUUCAAAUACAUAAGAAUAGAGUGGAUGAAAUGAAAAUAUUGCCUGUUUUGGGAUCACAAACAGGAAAAAUAUGAACAUGAUAUUUUAUAGCUUGGGAAGAAACUUGCAGAUGAUAUGUGCUGCCUUUGCUUCUUAUCAUUCAUGGCAGAUUGUUUGUGCUUUCAACAUUUCAUUUGAAAUGGGAGAAGAUAAAAUCACUUGAUGUAACCUGGAAACUAUGCUUUACAUGGCAAUCAAAGCCUUUUGAUCAUGUACAUUUUAUUUGAUAUUAAAAUCUUUUAUAACCAGAUACUGUCUGUGUUUCAUAUAUUUUUAAAAGUUUUGAUUGUUGGAAUGUUAUAUGAUCUUAAGGUCUGUAUAGACAA